AGGCCCCCGAACUUGACCUCCAGUCGGCCUCUGCAGGCCUGGCCUCCUGCCUCCCGAAAGCUUGCACAGGCCCAGCCUCUGCCUCACAGCGGACUCUCCACGCCCAGCUCGCUCUCGCCUGCGGCCUCCCGAGUCCAAAGCUCCGGCCUCUCCGCCGCUUCGGCAGGCCCAGCUCCCGCCUGCCAGUGGCCUCUUCAGGCCCAUGGGGCUCAUUCCUCACAACGGCCUUUCCCGGCCCAGUUUUUCCCUUCCGGCGGCCUCUCCGGGCCCAGAAGCUCCUCAAGUCGGCCUCUCCAGACCCACUUGCAGCCUCCCGGCGUCCUCUCCGGGCCCAGCUCUUCCUCCCGGCUGCGUCUGCAGGCCCGACUCCUGCCUCCCAACAACGUCUUUGGACUCAGUGCCUGCCCAGCUCGUGGUGGCCUUGGUCGGCCCACAGCUUCCUCAAGCCAAGCUCCCCAGGCCCAGCUCAGGCCUCACGGUGGCCUCUCCAGGCUCAGCUCCUGCCCUCCGACGGCGUCUCCAGGCCCCAAACGGCCUCCGGUCGGUGGGCUUCUCCAGGCCCAGCUUGGGCCUCCCGGCGGCCUCUGCAGGCCCAAGUGGUCCUGAAGUCAGCCUCUCCAGGCCCAGCUCCGGCCUCCCAGCAAGCAAGCUCUUUUGGCUCAGCUCCUGCCCAGCUCCCGCCGGUUUUUGUAGACCCUGA